GGAAGUGCGGUGUUUUAGCCGGUGGCUGCUGUCUCUGGGCGGGCCGUGGGAGGCUCCCGAGGUGGGGGCCGGGGCGGGAUGGCUGCAGCGGCGGCCGGGGCCGGGAGCGGGCCCUGGGCGGCCCAGGAGAAGCAGUUCCCGCCGGCGCUGCUGAGUUUCUUCAUCUACAACCCGCGCUUCGGGCCGCGCGAAGGACAGGAGGAAAAUAAGAUUUUAUUUUAUCAUCCAAAUGAGGUAGAAAAGAAUGAGAAGAUUAGAAAUGUCGGAUUGUGUGAAGCUAUUGUACAGUUUACAAGGACAUUUAGCCCAUCAAAACCUGCAAAAUCUUUACAUACACAGAAGAACAGACAGUUCUUCAAUGAACCAGAAGAAAAUUUCUGGAUGGUCAUGGUUGUUCGGAAUCCUAUAAUUGAAAAACAGAGUAAAGAUGGAAAACCAGUUAUUGAAUAUCAAGAGGAGGAGUUGUUGGACAAGGUUUAUAGCUCGGUGCUGCGGCAGUGCUACAGCAUGUACAAGCUUUUUAAUGGUACAUUUCUGAAAGCCAUGGAAGACGGAGGCGUCAAGCUUCUGAAAGAAAGAUUAGAGAAAUUCUUCCAUCGGUAUUUGCAAACGCUACAUUUGCAGUCAUGUGACCUACUUGACAUUUUUGGUGGAAUCAGCUUCUUCCCGUUGGAUAAAAUGACUUAUUUGAAAAUCCAGUCCUUUAUUAAUAGAAUGGAGGAAAGCCUGAAUAUAGUCAAAUACACUGCUUUUCUCUAUAACGAUCAGCUCAUCUGGAGUGGAUUAGAACAAGAUGACAUGAGAAUUUUAUACAAAUACCUUACCACCUCCCUUUUCCCAAGGCACAUCGAACCUGAGUUAGCAGGAAGGGAUUCUCCAAUAAGAGCAGAAAUGCCAGGAAAUCUUCAACACUAUGGAAGAUUUCUUACCGGACCCUUGAACCUCAAUGAUCCAGAUGCAAAAUGCAGAUUCCCCAAAAUUUUUGUAAAUACAGAUGACACUUAUGAAGAGCUCCAUUUAAUCGUUUAUAAGGCCAUGAGUGCGGCUGUGUGCUUUAUGAUCGACGCCUCUGUCCACCCAACGUUGGAUUUUUGCCGAAGACUGGACAGCAUCGUUGGGCCCCAGCUCACAGUGCUGGCCUCUGACAUCUGUGAACAGUUUAACAUCAACAAGAGGAUGUCUGGGUCUGAGAAAGAACCCCAGUUUAAGUUUAUCUACUUCAACCACAUGAAUCUCGCCGAGAAGAGCACAGUUCACAUGAGGAAAACGCCCAGCGUGUCGCUCACUUCCGUGCACCCGGAUUUAAUGAAGAUUCUCGGUGACAUCAACAGUGACUUUACCAGAGUGGAUGAAGAUGAGGAGAUCAUUGUGAAGGCCAUGAGUGAUUACUGGGUUGUUGGAAAGAAGUCUGAUCGGCGGGAGCUCUAUGUUAUUUUGAAUCAAAAAAAUGCAAACCUGAUUGAAGUAAAUGAAGAGGUCAAGAAACUUUGUGCAACGCAGUUCAACAACAUCUUCUUCUUGGAUUGACGGAUGACGGCUCACCGAGAGCAUAUCUAAAAAACACUCUGCAAACAUUUGGUCACAUGCAAGUUAGUGGUCAUAUGACGGACUGCAUUCAGGACAAGGGUAAAGCAAUACUUGCUUUGAAGAAUCAGAUUUCGACUCGGUCUGCUGAUCUGAGGUUUUUAGAUUUUAAAUAUUUAUGUGGAAUUAAUUAAAGGUAGUUGGCUAUAUCGCUAUCAUUUCAUUCUUUUGACAUUAUUUGAAUAUUUUACUGGAAAAUAAGACUAAUAAAUUGUUAAAAGUUUUUAAAA